GCCGAGUCCCCUGCCAGAUUGUCCAGAGUUGUACAAGGGCACAGUGCUGCCUCUCAAUGACAGGAAAUAGGUAUGAUUUCCUCUCUCUUCUUUGUCCUUAUUUCAUCUCUGAUUAUUGUCUUCCCAGCAUUUAACCACAUUUGCAAGUUACGUUUUUCACUUAUUUGUUGACCUGUUCAUGAUAUUCAUUAAUCCUGUAGAUUAAGAUCUUCAGGGAUUGUUAUCAGUUUCACUUAUUCUUUUAUCAUAUGGUCCCAGGAUACUGCCUGGCACAUAGUAGAUGUUCAGAAAUAUGGACUAAAUGAGUAUUAUAAUUGACACAUCUCAGUCAAGAAGGAGUGGCAGUUAUACUCAGUUGUAACUUUUUCUUGAAGAUAUGUAUCUUCAAGUUACUUGUACUAAUGGGUGGUUGCAUAUUUUGGCUCUUUUACUUUGUAUUUUUUUAGAAACAGGGUCUUACUUUGUCACCCAGCUUGGAGUGUGGUGGCAGGAUCACGGCUCACCACAGCUCACUCCUGGCUCACUCCUGGGCUCAAGUGAUCCUCCUGCCUCAGCCUUCCCUGUAGCCAGGACAACAGGCAUAUGCCAUCAUGCCUGGCUAAUUUUUAAAUUUUUUUUGUAGAUAUAGGAUCUCCCAAUGUUGCCUAGACUGGUCUUGAACUCCUGGUCUCAAGCCAUUCUCCUGUCUUGGCCAACCAAUUGUGAAACUGUGUCUGGCCUGUUUAACUCUUAAGUGUAGAUGUAAUUUACUUCAUGAAAGAGUCAGACUCAGUGGCUUAUACCUGUAAUCCUAGCCCUUUGUGGGAAGCUGAGGUGGGAGGAUUGCUUCAGGCCCUGAGUUUGAUACCAACGUGGGCAACAUAGCAAGACCCCCCCCCCCCCGACCAUCUCUAAAGAAAAUAAAAUGAAAAAAUAAGCUGGGCAUAGUGGUGAGCUCCUGUAGUCCCACUUCUCAGGAGGCUGAGGAGGGAGGAUCAGUUGAACCCAGGAGUUUGAAGCUGCAGUUAGCUAUGAUUGUACCACUGUAUUCCAGACUGGGCAACAGAGCCUGACCCUGUCUCUUAAAAAAAUAAAUAAAUAAGAAAAACAAGAAAGGGCUUCUUUCCUUCUGAGUGUGUGAGCAUCCCUCAUUUGAUGCAGAAGGUGAGGUGACACAGAAGUGGUCUCUGUCUCAGGGAUUAGCAAAUUUAGUAGGGAAAUGCCUCCAUAGCCCCCAAUUUACAUAUGAAUAGUUAAAAACUGACCGUUUCAUAAAAUAAGCCCUAACCAGGAAUGCAUUUUAAGGGAAUACUCUUGUGAUGAGUGGAUUUCCAGAGCAAAGAAGAGACACAGUCUGAGUUACCAGUGCCAAUUACUUGGUACCACUGCAAAUCAUUCCCCUUUGGCAACAUUAUUUUUAAAAUUAACUUUUAGGAAUUUCUUCUCCAAGCGUAUUCUUGGUUCGGCAUUCUAACAGUUCAUUUACCUGAUUGCAUUUGAUGGGUCUGUUGGGAUUCUGGAAUGUCAAUUUUACUUUUUAGGAGAUAGGUUGCCUGGGUCAUGUCCAACAUUCUUGUAGAUUGAAGAUAUUUUCCUUAGCUUCUUGUUCUUUGCUUUCUGGACUCACAUCCUUUAGUUGUUUUCGAUUUGGGGCUACUAUAAAAAAUGUUUUUACUUAUUCUCCAGAUAUUUUCUUCCAGCCAUAUGCCGGGCCCCUUUGUUUCAGGCACCCAGGAUAGAGUGGUGAACAAAUCCCUGCCUGCACAGAGCUGACAUUCUAGAACCUGUGUAGGGGAGAGAAGAUUCCUUUCCCUUACACAUCAAAAAGUUCAUGGCUGAGGCCCCCAUAACAGAUUAACAAGAGAAAAGCAAGCAUAUUUAUUGAAUAUCAGUUUUACGUGUCACAGGAGUUUUCAGAAAUGAAGACCCAAAGCAACGGGGAAAACUGUAUUUUUAUGGACAGUGGUGCCAAAGUAUGAUUGGAGGACAAAGGGGUAUUAUUGUCUACCGGUAAUAAACUGUGGGGGUGGAGGGGAGCCAGCAAGGCUUGUUUUGUUCAAUUUCUUCUUGGUGUCUCACAGAAAUAAGGACGUUCCUUUCCUCUGGGCAUGUGGAGGACCUCUCUAGAAUGAGGGUGAGACUAUGACCUACUUUCAGGGGAAGGUCAGUUAAGUUUUAUAACCAGUUUCAGGGGGAGAAGGGAUGAGAGAGGACCAGAGAGACCAUCCUGCUUUUGAUGUUCUCCCAAAGGCAAGGUGCUCCAUUUUGAGGCCAGGAGUUUGGUACUAGCUUGGGCAACAUAGCAAGAGCCCCCGUCUCUACACAAAAUAAAAUAAAAAAAUAAGCUGGGCAUGAUGGUGAGCUCCUGUAGUCCCACUACUCAGGAGGCUGAGGAGGGAGGAUCAGUUGAACCCAGGAGGUGUUCUCAACUCUGGCACAUGCUUGUAGCUGAAUUAUUGAUGAUGCCUUUGAUUUGUUUUCUUGGGAUUCAUUGUGCCCUAGUGUCUCCUGUAUGUGCCGUCCCUCAUGCCUUCAACUUUCUUUGCUCAAAAUGAAACCAAUUGAUGAUAAAUGAAAGGAUCAGUAGGCUUUAAAGCAGUUAUUUACAACUGAGCAUUUAGAGUUCCCACGCUUAAAAAGUGGGAGCUGUUCCCAUGGCUGCUGAGAGUGCUGCGGAAGCUGGUUCUCUUUGUCCUUAAGUUGAUCGAUAGCAGGCAUCAGCGGGGAAGAUGCUUUGUACUUUGCUUGUUAAACAGAGGGCUGCUAAGCAGCUGUGGCAGUGUGACCCUGGUUGUGCUGCUGUGGGUGACAUGAGUGUGCAUGUGGACAGUGGUUAUGGUGCUUCCCUACACACUGGGCACCCACCCUAUGGACAGACACACUCCAUGAAAAUGUUUGGGAAGUAUAAGAGCUCCAGGCCAUGGGAUGAAAUGGGAAGGACCUAACUCUGAUUUCUAGAUUUGGAAUUGAAUCUGCAUGUACUGUUCAGGUCAUUGUUCUGGCACAUAUUUGACGGUUUGGUUGUCUUCAAGCUCAGGGGCUGCGAAAGUUGCCAGAAUAGGAAUGUUCUGGCCUGAUGCAAGCAGGCACCCGGUGCCUGUGGAUUCAGGACUGGUCACACUGCAGCUGGACAUUAUGAAUUCAGAUGUCCCUGAUGAGACGGUGUCCUAGGACAGUGGCUAGGUGAGGUCUCAGGAUCUCAGGUACAAGGUUAGAGGAGGCAACGUGGAGUCACAGUGGAGAGCCUGGUUGGUCCCAUAGCCAGAUAGCUACAGGUUCAGGUACCAGCUCUGCCCUCAUCUAUUUUUUGUGACCUUGGGAAAGUUAGAUAACAAUUUGAGCUCCUUUUUCUAUCUUGAAAAUAGGGAUCUAAUGUCUAACUUAGCUCCCUGGUGUUUUAUUCUCCCCAUCUCAUCCACAUCACACUUUUAUUUUCAAGUCUUGUUUUCUUUCUGUCAUUUAUUCCCGAGAUAAGUGUAUGCUUGUUUUGUUGUUUAUUUUCCCAGCUAGGAUACAAGUUCUUUGCGAGUUAAGGAUUUGAUUGGUCUUGUUCACUGCUCUGUCUCAGCACCCAGCACCUACUAGGUGAAGUAUUUAUAGAAUGAAAGGAUGAGUUUGCUAGACACUCAUGGCCAUGAUCUAGUGCUCCCAGGUCCGUAUUUUUUGGCCAAAGCCAGAAAAAGACCAUCUUCAAGUAGAAACAUAGUUAUACGCCUGUAAAAAUUUGACACAUUAUAGAUUCUGGCCACCAUGCCCUUGGAACUUCACUUCUGAAUCUGUGUUCAGACCAGGAAUGUAGCACUGGUUCUCAUGGCUUGCUUUGGAGGAAGUCUUUGGAAAUUUUUGCUGAUAGCCUUCUACCUAGGAGCAUGAGUUCGGCUGUUUUCUCCUGCCCCUGCCCCUGCCCCUGCCCCUGUUCCCCUUUUUGGACAGUGCCCAAGACCUAGCAGACACACCUUGGGGCCCCUCUAGCCUGAAAGCCUUUGGUAAUCCCUGCUUUUAAGGGCCUUUUGCCAUGGCCUGAUGAACAUCAGACAGGAUGCUGAUGGUUUUAUUCUUGUAGCUCCAUAGCCGUCAGCCUGAAUAGAUGUUCUCAGGGCUUCAUAUAGGCAUAUACAAUGUAUGUUUUCUUUCAUCGACAAAGGCACUGAUGGUGCAAGUCCAAACAGUGCUGCUCAGUUGAGGAUUUUCUUGUUCAAUUUUCGGGAGCUCUUGACUGACUGCAUUCUGCUUCACUGGAGAAGAAGAUAGUUUGAUGAGGCUGUGUACACUUCUUAAAAGUGAAAAAGCCUUUGCAGGUUUGUCCAGACAGUGGGGUGACCAGGAAGGAGAGUCAGAAGAGAAGCGUUGACAGAAGGCUACGUUGGGGCCCUGCACGAGAAUAGACACGGCAGCGCAGUGCAGAUCCGCAGGCGCAAGGCUUCAGGCGACCCGUACUGGGCCUACUCUGGUGCCUAUGGUCCUGAGCACUGGGUCACGUCUAGUGUCAGCUGUGGGGGCCGUCACCAGUCUCCUAUUGACAUUUUAGACCAGUAUGCGCGUGUUGGGGAAGAAUACCAGGAACUGCAACUCGAUGGCUUCGACAAUGAGUCUUCUAACAAAACCUGGAUGAAAAACACAGGGAAAACAGUCGCCAUCCUUCUGAAAGACGACUAUUUUGUCAGUGGAGCUGGUCUACCUGGCAGAUUCAAAGCUGAGAAGGUGGAAUUUCACUGGGGCCACAGCAAUGGCUCAGCGGGCUCUGAACACAGCAUCAAUGGCAGGAGGUUUCCUGUUGAGAUGCAGAUUUUCUUUUACAAUCCAGAUGACUUUGACAGCUUUCAAACCGCAAUUUCUGAGAACAGAAUAAUCGGAGCCAUGGCCAUAUUUUUUCAAGUCAGUCCGAGGGACAAUUCUGCACUGGAUCCUAUUAUCCACGGGUUGAAGGGUGUCGUACAUCAUGAGAAGGAGACCUUUCUGGAUCCUUUCGUCCUCCGGGACCUCCUGCCUGCAUCCCUGGGCAGCUAUUAUCGGUACACAGGUUCCUUGACCACACCACCGUGUAGCGAAAUAGUGGAGUGGAUAGUCUUCCGGAGACCCGUCCCCAUCUCUUACCAUCAGCUUGAGGCUUUUUAUUCCAUCUUCACCACGGAGCAGCAAGACCAUGUCAAGUCGGUGGAGUAUCUGAGAAAUAACUUUCGACCACAGCAGCGUCUGCAUGACAGGGUGGUGUCCAAGUCCGCCGUCCGUGACUCCUGGAACCACGACAUGACAGACUUCUUAGAAAACCCACUGGGGACAGAAGCCUCUAAAGUUUGCAGCUCUCCACCCAUCCACAUGAAGGUGCAGCCUCUGAACCAGACGGCACUGCAGGUGUCCUGGAGCCAGCCGGAGACUAUCUACCACCCACCCAUCAUGAACUACAUGAUCUCCUACAGCUGGACCAAGAAUGAGGACGAGAAGGAGAAGACGUUUACAAAGGACAGCGACAAAGACUUGAAAGCCACCAUUAGCCAUGUCUCACCCGAUAGCCUUUACCUGUUCCGAGUCCAGGCCGUGUGUCGGAACGACAUGCGCAGCGACUUUAGCCAGACGAUGCUGUUUCAAGCUAAUACCACUCGAAUAUUCCAAGGGACCAGAAUAGUGAAAACAGGAGUGCCCACAGCGUCUCCUGCCUCUUCAGCCGACAUGGCCCCCAUCAGCUCGGGGUCUUCUACCUGGACGUCCUCUGGCAUCCCAUUCUCAUUUGUUUCCAUGGCAACUGGGAUGGGCCCCUCCUCCAGUGGCAGCCAGGCCACAGUGGCCUCGGUGGUCACCAGCACGCUGCUCGCCGGCCUGGGGUUCGGCGGUGGUGGCAUCUCCUCUUUCCCCAGCACUGUGUGGCCCACGCGCCUCCCGACGGCCGCCUCAGCCAGCAAGCAGGCGGCUAGGCCAGUCCUAGCCACCACAGAGGCCUUGGCUUCUCCAGGGCCCGAUGGUGAUUCGUCACCAACCAAGGACGGCGAGGGCACCGAGGAAGGAGAGAAGGAUGAGAAAAGCGAGAGUGAGGAUGGGGAGCGGGAGCACGAGGAGGAUGGAGAGAAGGACUCCGAAAAGAAGGAGAAGAGUGGGGUGACCCACGCUGCCGAGGAGCGGAAUCAGACGGAGCCCAGCCCCACACCCUCGUCUCCUAACAGGACUGCCGAGGGAGGGCAUCAGACUAUACCUGGGCAUGAGCAGGAUCACACUGCCGUCCCCACAGACCAGACGGGCGGAAGGAGGGAUGCCGGCCCAGGCCUGGACCCCGACAUGGUCACCUCCACCCAAGUGCCCCCCACCGCCACAGAGGAGCAGUAUGCAGGGAGUGAUCCCAAGAGGCCCGAAAUGCCAUCUAAAAAGCCUAUGUCCCGCGGGGACCGAUUUUCUGAAGACAGCAGAUUUAUCACUGUUAAUCCAGCGGAAAAAAACACCUCUGGAAUGAUAAGCCGCCCUGCUCCAGGGAGGAUGGAGUGGAUCAUCCCUCUGAUUGUGGUAUCAGCCUUGACCUUCGUGUGCCUCAUCCUUCUCAUUGCUGUGCUCGUUUACUGGAGAGGGUGUAACAAAAUAAAGUCCAAGGGCUUUCCCAGACGUUUCCGUGAAGUGCCUUCUUCUGGGGAGAGAGGAGAGAAGGGGAGCAGAAAAUGUUUUCAGACUGCUCAUUUCUAUGUGGAAGACAGCAGUUCACCUCGAGUGGUCCCUAAUGAAAGUAUCCCUAUUAUUCCUAUUCCGGAUGACAUGGAAGCCAUUCCUGUCAAACAGUUUGUCAAACACAUCGGUGAGCUCUAUUCUAAUAACCAGCAUGGGUUCUCUGAGGAUUUUGAGGAAGUCCAGCGCUGUACUGCUGAUAUGAACAUCACUGCAGAGCAUUCCAAUCAUCCAGAAAACAAGCACAAAAACAGAUACAUCAACAUUUUAGCAUAUGAUCACAGUAGGGUGAAGUUAAGACCUUUACCAGGAAAAGACUCUAAGCACAGCGACUACAUUAAUGCAAACUAUGUUGAUGGUUACAACAAAGCAAAAGCCUACAUUGCCACCCAAGGACCUUUGAAGUCUACAUUUGAAGAUUUCUGGAGGAUGAUUUGGGAACAAAACACUGGAAUCAUUGUGAUGAUUACGAACCUUGUGGAAAAAGGAAGACGAAAAUGUGAUCAGUAUUGGCCAACAGAGAACAGUGAGGAAUAUGGAAACAUUAUUGUCACGCUGAAGAGCACAAAAAUACAUGCCUGCUACACUGUUCGUCGUUUUUCAAUCAGAAAUACAAAAGUGAAAAAGGGUCAGAAGGGAAAUCCCAAGGGUCGUCAGAAUGAAAGGGUAGUGAUCCAGUAUCACUAUACACAGUGGCCUGACAUGGGAGUUCCCGAGUAUGCCCUUCCAGUACUGACUUUCGUGAGGAGAUCCUCAGCAGCUCGGAUGCCAGAAACGGGCCCUGUGUUGGUGCACUGCAGUGCUGGUGUGGGCAGAACAGGCACCUAUAUUGUAAUAGACAGCAUGCUGCAACAGAUAAAAGACAAAAGCACAGUUAACGUCCUGGGAUUCCUGAAGCAUAUCAGGACACAGCGUAACUACCUCGUCCAGACUGAGGAGCAGUACAUUUUCAUCCAUGAUGCCUUGUUGGAAGCCAUUCUUGGAAAGGAGACUGAAGUAUCUUCAAAUCAGCUGCACAGCUAUGUUAACAGCAUCCUUAUACCAGGAGUAGGAGGAAAGACACGACUGGAAAAGCAAUUCAAGCUGGUCACACAGUGUAAUGCAAAAUAUGUGGAAUGUUUCAGUGCUCAGAAAGAGUGUAACAAAGAAAAGAACAGAAACUCUUCAGUUGUGCCAUCUGAGCGUGCUCGAGUGGGUCUUGCACCAUUGCCUGGAAUGAAAGGAACAGAUUACAUUAAUGCUUCUUAUAUCAUGGGCUAUUAUAGGAGCAAUGAAUUUAUUAUAACUCAGCAUCCUCUGCCACAUACUACGAAAGAUUUCUGGCGAAUGAUUUGGGAUCAUAACGCACAGAUCAUUGUCAUGCUGCCAGACAACCAGAGCUUGGCAGAAGAUGAGUUUGUGUACUGGCCAAGUCGAGAAGAAUCCAUGAACUGUGAGGCCUUUACCGUCACCCUUAUCAGCAAAGACAGACUGUGCCUCUCUAAUGAAGAACAAAUUAUCAUCCAUGACUUUAUCCUUGAAGCUACACAGGAUGACUAUGUCUUAGAAGUUCGGCACUUUCAGUGUCCCAAAUGGCCUAACCCAGAUGCCCCCAUAAGUAGUACCUUUGAACUUAUCAACGUCAUCAAGGAAGAGGCCUUAACAAGGGAUGGUCCCACCAUUGUUCAUGAUGAGUAUGGAGCAGUUUCAGCAGGAAUGUUAUGUGCCCUUACCACCCUGUCCCAGCAACUGGAGAAUGAAAAUGCUGUGGAUGUUUUCCAGGUUGCAAAAAUGAUCAAUCUUAUGAGGCCUGGAGUAUUCACAGACAUUGAACAAUACCAGUUCAUCUAUAAAGCAAUGCUUAGCUUGGUCAGCACUAAAGAAAAUGGAAAUGGUCCCAUGACAGUAGACAAAAAUGGUGCUGUUCUUAUUGCAGAUGAAUCAGACCCUGCUGAGAGCAUGGAGUCCCUAGUGUGACUGGAAUCCUGAAAGGGCACUUAAUUUGUAAACUUCUGAAGACUGAGAACUUUUUUGAGGCCUUUUUUGCCAGACUCUAGGUUAUACAAUAACCCAGUUACUUUUUUACACUGAUAAAAGUUUUGAUAUUUAUUUUUUGCCAUUUUAUGUCUUAAUGGUAUCCUACUGAGCAUUUGCACCUCUGUUCAUUUCACACAGUGAAACGCAAUUUUACCUAGUUUGCACUAUAUGAUCAGUGUUACUGCCUAUAAUCUUAUACAACAGCAAACCCUGAUGUGACAUUCCAUGACGACAUACAUGCUACUUUUUUUUAGUUCAAUACAGUGAAGGUCUUUGUUAUGACAGUGAAUAUUGCUUUUAUUAUUAUUAUUGCUGAAGUGGUUGCAUUCUACUAGCAGGCAAUGCUGUACUUUUCUUCAGUCCUCCUCUCCUUUUUAUUUUAGGCACUGUUCAAUACUGUAUGCCUUCUGUAUUUUAAUGGAGUGGAUAGCAUUGUUUUCUUUUACAGACUAGCAGGCUACUGGGACCUAAAAAGGUCUGUUAAUGUCAUGGCCUUGAAACAGUUCCAUUUAUGCUGGUUAAGAGAUCCCUUAAGAAGUUAGAAGGCUUAAGAACUGCUUCAUGUGAACAUCCCUUAUUAGUUACAAAGUUAUAUUCACAGUUUUUUAAAAAUGUGUCAAAAUAAAGGAUAACUCUGUAUUACAGCUUUCACAGUAGCUAUGUGGACAAUGUGUUAUUUCCAUUUUGACUCUCUAAAAUAGCUACAUCCUAAAAUCAGGGCUAUCUUUAACAAUAGCAAGAUAGCAAUAUUAUAUACAACUCAGUUAUGAGACCCUUUAGUUAUUCUCCAUUAAUGCUUCUUAGUUUGUAAUACCAUACCUCACAGUAGGUAGAAGAAUGAAAACUUCUGCAGGUGUGUAAUUUUGAAACUAGUCCUCUAAAAAUUCCCUAUUACUCCUAUAGCAAUCUAAUAAAAACUACCUACAUAGUUACUGUUUUCUUUCCUUCUUUGCCAAAUGUUUUAUAAUAAAUCUCUUAAUUACAUACAUUUUUCUACUUAAGAUUAAAUUGGAAAUACUGUCUUAGCAAAAGUCUUGGGACUAUCUAAACUCCCACACAUAGAUAAAUCUGAUUUGGAGAGAGAAAUUUAAAAUAUUUAAUUAAAGGUGAUACCCACAUUUUCAAGUUUUUAAAAGAGGGAGAUGGCUUUGUAUGCUUUUGUGUAGUUUAGAACAGAUACACAUUAGUAAAAGAUACCAAUAAUCAUUAGAGCUCAAGGAAGUUAUUAGGUGCAGCCUCUGGAGCCAUACUCACGCUGCAGUGCAUAAUGGGAAAAUUAGGAGCAUUAAUAAGAAAUUUCAGUAGUGUUUGUAAGGAAAAUAAGCUACUUACUGAGAUCUGUUUCUUCUAUUGCAUGUUUGCUUUUGAGGGACAGCUUCUGUCAAAAGUGAAAUCAUCACCAGAACUGGGCCUGUUAGGAAGAAUAGGGUUUUAUUUACUUUUUAUGUCAAUUAACUUCAACAAAAAGGCCACGCUGGCUGCUGUCAUGCCAUCUGGGUAUGCAUUAAACAUUAAUGAUGAUCAGCACUGAGGUUCUAUUUAUCUUGAUUUGGCUUUCAUAAAGUUUGUCAGAAUGGUGCUGGAGGACCAGAAGUGCUAAGGAGAAAGAAGCUAUGGGCCAAGUUAAAGAAUUUGAAUGCAAAGGCCAGGUCAAUGGAGUUUUCAUAAACUACAUAAUUUACCAGGGUUUAUCUCAUCUUCUCAAUACAUAGAUUUAACAACAUGGAAUACUCUGCUUUUCAAGAGCUGCGUAAGCUAGUCCUGAGAUAAGAUGUUCAAGAGAGCAUGCUAAGUUGCAUGUGCUAGAUGAGAGACACCUUUACAGCCCCUCCGCUCCAACCAGAGGUGACACAGGAAGCUCUGUAAAGUUCAAGUAAAGCUUGAACACAGGAACACUACAACUGCCAGAUGCUGAGGAGAAUCAGGAAAGCAAUGAGCUAGACUCUUUUUUUAGUCAAUUAAGUGGGUUGUUUUAGAUGUAUAGAGUAUUGAUAUGAGUUAACACUUUUUAGUAGAUGGCAAAGUGGGCUUGAUGUUCAAAAGUAAUGUUCGAGUUAGGGUUCAUGGUCCCUUUCUCAGUAAUUUUUUCUUAAUAAAAGUAAACACUGGUUCAAAGACAAAUAGCAAGUAUUCCCUCCUGUGCUAUUUAUAGAGGGCUCAAUUCGUAGAAAGGCAUACCCUCCAAUGCAAUUCUGUGGCUGUCCCUUACAGUGGUUUCAGAAUCACGAAAAAACAGCUAGUAAAUAGGAUAGAAACAAUAAAAGAAAGAGUUUAGAAGUUCCCUGUGAGCAAUCUGUGUGUCUUCAGCGAGCUUGAACCAAAGUCUUCAUAUCCUGACCCACUGAAUUAUAAGCAAUUGCUACUUGCCCAUCUUGCCAAAGUAGUCCAAACACACUUCAAUGAGGACAGUUAUAUUUAGCAGGUCCUCACCCCUGCAAGAGACAGCAUAUCCUCACUAUUAUUAUUCAUGUGUUAUUGGCAAAAACAUAGCUUGCAUCUUUCCAGAGGCAGAGUUUCAAAGACAGGGUUUUCUUUGAGACAUAAGCACAUUGCUUAAGUACAUAACAAGGUUAUUAACACUUGCACUCAGGGGAAAGGAAAUAGCUAUUGCAAAUUAAUGUGUGCAACUUAAUAAAAUAAGCUGUUUGUGUAUAUGAAUUUAGCUCUAGGUAAGCAAAAUGCACACAUCAUAUAAAAAUAAAUUGCAAUGAUCAGACCAAGUGGCUGUGCUGGACAUCAAAGAAAAGACAUGCUGUUGCCAUCAGGAGAACUCUUUCUUAUAUGCGAUAGCCAAGAUAUCUUCUUUAAUAUGAAAAAAGUUAAUUUCUGAAUUUCAAAAAGAGUAAGAUUAGCUAAUUGGUCUUCCUAAUUUUUAUGCCUUUAGAGUUUUUAGUCUAUUCAAGUAGAAGAGUCCAGCGAGGCCAAAGAAGGGUUACGGUGUUCAAGUUCUGGUUGUUGGAGUUUUUAGCCCAGAGUGACAUACUGAAAUCAGUAAAUAAUUAUUUUAUAAUGACACAGCACAACUGCCUUGUUAUGAAUUUUUCUUAAAUGCAUAUAUACUGUAUUUAAAAUUAAAAUAUAGAUACCAAUUUACCAAAGAUACAUAUUACUAAUUCUAAGCAAAACUAAAAAAAAAACCCAACUCAUCAUAAUUUAAGAAUCAAAAUGUAGUUUGUCUUAAGAAUUUAGUGGUUAUACUGGAAAUGCAUUUUCAACUCCUAUGUUCUAAAGUUUAUGUUCAAAUGGUGCCAGUGAAUUUUUAUAUGAAGGGAAAAUGCCUGCUUUUUUUUUUUUUUUAACAGAUGUAAUUUCACUUAACCCUUUGCGCUUUCCCUUAGUUGUCAUUUAACAUACAAUACUGGCUUUACUUAUCUCUAGAAAGAAGAAGGCAUGCUACAAAUAGGAAGGAAUUGUAAUAAUGAUAUUUGGCCUCUACUUUGUCUUAGCUGUUAAACUGUUUUUAGUAUUUUUGUUAAAUAUUUGCAAAGGGAAGCAUUUUCUACAGAGGAUAAUUAAUUUCAAGAAAAAUAUCUUGAGUUUUAAGAAAUAAACAUCUCCAGAAAAGGAGAAAGUCGAUUUUAUAAAAUGUCGCAACUCUCCAACAUUUGGGGUAGUGACUCCUUUUUUGUUAGGACAUUUGAAACUAGCAAGCAGCCAUUGUUUCUAAAGAAUUCUGGCUUCACAUUGACUCAUGUUUCUUUCACUCCAUUUUGAAAUAGCUAAAAAUCAUUAAAACUGUAAAUAUUUUGUUGCUUGGGUAAGCAUCUUCUGGGAACUUUGUAUCUAUGGUAUAUAAUCAUAGAAUUUUAUAUUUUCAUAUAAAGCUAAUUUUUUUCUAGUUUCAACUCCGUCAUAGUUUUUUUUCCUUUUUGUGGUGGAUAUGUGAAUUCAACUUUCUGUGUAUUGAAGUAGCAAAAACCAUCUUUACAUUCCAAAAGAAUCCAACAUGUGUUAUUUCUUUGAGGCAGUGAUUGUGAAAGUUGGGUUUUCUUUUUAAUUCCAUUGACCAUUUGUGCAAUAGGAAUUAGACAUAAUUAGUCACUGAAAACAUUCGUCACAUUGACCCAUUUGGAAAAAGUGUGCUUUUUUUUUUUUUUUAAAUUUGUUCAGGGGGAGGGGUUUUGUAACCUGAAAUUUUUCCCUUUUUCUUCUGUUUAAACUAUAUCAAAUCAUUCUAUUAUAGUGUUAUUUAAUAUGUAAAUUGUAUUGCUAUACAUAAAAUAAAGUAUGGUUUUUGAUGUA